ACUCGGCCAGGCGCCGGCGACCUGAGGGGAGAGGGAACGCAGCUGAAAGCGUGAACUGUGUGGUUGCACAAUUCCCCUCUGCCUUCCUGUGGGGUGUCAUCAUAGCCUGGUCAAUGAGAAGUUGGGUAACUUCCCAGAGGGUCACGGAGGGAGUGGGUGGCCAAGGCAGGAAGAACAGAAGCCAACCCCGCCCACAGUGGGAACCCAGGCGUUAGGUAGAGUCCUCACGCCGGUGUAAACUGACUAGCAACGAGUUACAGGCAAAAAAGCUGUGCUUUUCUAGAAGUAGAAAGGGGGAGGAUAAUCAAAGAAGAGCUGUGCCUUUAUUGUUAUGCUAUAACGAGCAAAAGUAAAGCAGCCUUGCUAUGUAAAGUGGUGUUUAUCUCACCUCACAGGAGAUGCUUUUGACAAGUUAUAAUAAGGGAGAGAUGGUAGUAAAGGAAGUGAAGAAGCGACGUGAAAUUGAAGGAAAAGAAAAUGACCUGCCUUCUUACCGCGGUUGGAAUACACACCCAAACGAGAGGUAGCAGAGAAGCAAGCAGUGCAUUCUGUUAAAAAUUAUUGUGUCCUCAUUUGAGAGAGGAGGGAUCCUCAAAUAAUACAACUAUGUGCAAAGCAGGAAGUGAAAUCCUUCUCAGUCCUCUCCCCAGUUGUAAUCCAAGCCUUCCACAUCUUUCCUGUAUGUGCAUAACCAUGUUAUUUUGCUUUCUUAUGAAAAUGAGAUUAUGCAUACUGUUCGAUAAUCUGUUUCAGAUUAAAUAUAUAUAUAUGGUGAAAGUCUUGCCAUAUGUAGCUCUAUUUUAUUGUAAUGUUGGCGUGGUACUGCAUUGUGUAGAUGUACCAAAUUAUAGUUAACUGUCACUUACUAUGUCCUGUCCGUAUAUAUUGCCCAGUAUUCUUCAAAAUUAUCUGUUUCUCAUUAGACUACAGAUUUCAUUAAUCCUUUGUGAAAUAUAUGGCAAAUAUUUUCAAGAAUUAUCAAUGCUUUGGUUUAAAAUGCCCAGGCUUUUUAUCUCAGGUAAGAAGGUAGUCCCCACUCAAAAAUUCUUAAAAUCUUCUCCUAUAUUGCCUGUUAAUUCUCUUUUUAUGAUUUACUCAUUAAAACAUCUGAAAAUGAUUUUUGUAUGCUAAGAUAAGGAUUUAAUUUUUUUCUUUGUUUUUAUGACUAGGCAGCCAUUUUUUCCUGAAAUCAUUUGUUGAAAUCAUUUCUCUCCCAACUGACUAGAAAUACCUCCUUAAUAUAGUAAAUUCUCAAGUGUACAUGCAUCUUUUCUUUAGACUCAUCUGUUGCUUUGAUCUUUUUGUCUCUUCCUUUAAAAAUACCAAUCUGCUUUGAUAUUACGUUUUCUAGUAAUUCAUAGGACAAGUCCCUCUUCAUUUUUCCUUUUCAAAAUUUUCUUGAAUAUAAUUGCAUUAUCUUUGAGAUAAAAUUUAACAUAAACUGUUCAUGCUUCAUUAAAAUACUCUUUUUGGGAUUUAACCAUUAUAUUUUCUUAUAUUUUGUGACUGGUAUGUAGAUGAGUGUUUAUGUAUCUGGCCAACUUUCUAAAUUUAUUAAUUUUAAUAAAUUGUUUCACUUGAAUUUUCUAGGAAAACAAUCAUCUAAUUAUAAUUCAUCUUAUCUCUUUCUUUCUUUGCUUUAGUGAAUUGCUGGCUUCCCCAGAAUAGUGGUAAAUAAAACAGUGAUUCUGGCCAUCCUUUAUCUUGUUUCUUAGUUUGGGGAUGUUUUUAUUAUGUCAUCAUUAAAUAUGAAGUUACUAUUAAUAUCUAAUAAAUUAUAUUUAUCAGGGAAGUUUCCUUUAAUAUUUCUAGCUCAUUGUGAUUUUUGCAGAGAACUGUUUGGAUUGCAUCCAAAGUCAUUUUUGCAACUGGGGAUGGGGAGUGUCUAUUGUAUUAGAUAGCACUUUGAGAACAAUUUUAAAUAAUAGAUAUUGGAUGUUCAUUUGGUGUGUAUAUUCAUUACUUCUUAACAUUUUUAUCAGGAAUGGAAGUUGGAUUUUGUCAAAUGGCUUUUUGACAUCUAUCAUAACCUUUCAUAGGUACUUUUCAUCUUUGACCUAACAGGAUAGUGAAUUACUUUAGUAUAUUUGCAGUUUGUGAACCAAUCUUACGCUUGGUCAUGGUGUAAUAUUUAAGUAUAUAUUGGUUCCUUUGGUAGCAUUUUUAUUUAAAAUCAAUGAUUGAGAUUCAUUUUAUACUCACCUUUUUCUGUUAUUUUUGCUAGGUUUUGGUAUCAAGGUUAUGCUGGUUCCUAAAAAGAACUGGGCAGAGUUCCUCUUCCUCCGCUCUGAUGUAGUUUAAAUAGCCUAAGAACUCUGCUCUUUGAAGAUCUGAAAGAAUUCACUCAUGAAACCAUGUGGGUCUGGGAGUUCAUUGUUCUUAAGACAGCAACAAUACUCAGCAAAAUGGUUCAGAACAAACAAAAACUCCUUGGAGUAAAUACAAUUGAAUGAAAGAGUCUGGGACACGGUAAUGUCAAGAACUAAGAACAGCUGCUGUACUGAUGCUGGUUAUUUCCCCCCUACACACAACUUUUUUUUCAUGGACAAGGAAAAAUGCUGUAGACCUGUCAUUUACUCCAUCCUUUAUAGUGAUGCUACAGGACGAAGAGGAAUGGAUAAAAACAUUGGCGAGCAACUCAAUAAAGCGUAUGAAGCCUUCCGGCAGGCAUGCAUGGAUAGAGAUUCUGCAGUAAAAGAAUUACAGCAAAAGACUGAGAACUAUGAGCAGAGAAUACGUGAACAACAGGAACAGCUGUCACUUCAACAGACUAUUAUUGACAAGCUAAAAUCUCAGUUACUUCUUGUGAAUUCCACUCAAGAUAACAAUUAUGGCUGUGUUCCUCUGCUUGAAGACAGUGAAACAAGAAAGAAUAAUUUGACUCUUGAUCAGCCACAAGAUAAAGUGAUUUCAGGAAUAGCAAGAGAAAAACUACCAAAGGUAAGAAGACAAGAGGUUUCUUCUCCUAGAAAAGAAACUUCAGCAAGGAGUCUUGGCAGUCCUUUGCUCCAUGAAAGGGGUAAUAUAGAGAAGACUUUCUGGGAUCUGAAAGAAGAAUUUCAUAAAAUAUGCAUGCUAGCAAAAGCACAGAAAGACCACUUAAGCAAACUUAAUAUACCAGACACUGCAACUGAAACACAGUGCUCUGUGCCUAUACAGUGUACGGAUAAAACAGAUAAACAAGAAGCGCUGUUUAAGCCUCAGGCUAAAGAUGAUAUAAAUAGAGGUGCACCAUCCAUCACAUCUGUCACACCAAGAGGACUGUGCAGAGAUGAGGAAGACACCUCUUUUGAAUCACUUUCUAAAUUCAAUGUCAAGUUUCCACCUAUGGACAAUGACUCAACUUUCUUACAUAGCACUCCAGAGAGACCCGGCAUCCUUAGUCCUGCCACGUCUGAGGCAGUGUGCCAAGAGAAAUUUAAUAUGGAGUUCAGAGACAACCCAGGGAACUUUGUUAAAACAGAAGAAACUUUAUUUGAAAUUCAGGGAAUUGACCCCAUAGCUUCAGCUAUACAAAACCUUAAAACAACUGACAAAACAAAGCCCUCAAAUCUCGUAAACACUUGUAUCAGGACAACUCUGGAUAGAGCUGCGUGUUUGCCACCUGGAGACCAUAAUGCAUUAUAUGUAAAUAGCUUCCCACUUCUGGACCCAUCUGAUGCACCUUUUCCCUCACUCGAUUCCCCGGGAAAAGCAAUCCGAGGACCACAGCAGCCCAUUUGGAAGCCCUUUCCUAAUCAAGACAGUGACUCGGUGGUACUAAGUGGCACAGACUCAGAACUGCAUAUACCUCGAGUAUGUGAAUUCUGUCAAGCAGUUUUCCCACCAUCCAUUACAUCCAGGGGGGAUUUCCUUCGGCAUCUUAAUUCACACUUCAAUGGAGAGACUUAAGACACAUUUGAAAACAGACAUAUCAAGUUCUAUGUGAUGAUUUUGGGUUUUUAAUACUAUAAAUACUUGAUUGUAAACUAAAUUCAAGAUCAUUUAUAGGAAAAUCUAGUUUCACAGCUAUUUGAAUUUUUUUCUGGAUUUACUAUAUAACUCUUAUUUUUUAAAAGAUCAUUCUGUUCUUUCAAGGAGAAAUAAGCCUAAAAGAAGAAAAACAAAAAAAAUUCUGUAUAAAACUGUAAUCCUUUGUAUUCAUGUUUACAGUGCUAUUACUAUAAUUCAAAAUUAUGUAUGUGACUUAGAGUUAUAUAAUCAUAAUUUAUGUUUAUUUCAAAUAUCUAAGUUUAUUGCUUGGAUUUCUAGUGAGAGCUGUUGAAUUUGGUGAUGUCAAAUGUUUCUAGGGUUUUUUUAGUUUGUUUUUAUUGAAAAAUUUAAUUAUUUAUGCUAUAGGUGAUAUUCUCUUUGAAUAAACCUAUAAUAGAAAAUAGCAGACAACAUAAACAUCUUUGUAAAUAUCAAACCUAAUACAUUUCUUGUCCAGUGAUAAAACAACUGGUAGAAUUAUUUAAACACUUUAGAUUUUUAAAUAAUAUACAUGGCUUUAAUUUUUACUGUGUGUAUAGCUACAUGAUGAAAUUAAUUAAAUAUUAAGAGGUACUUAUGUUGUGAUCAUUUGUAUGUCCUUUGUUCCUGAGUAAAAAAAAAAAAAAAAAAA